AGAGCAAGCGGAAGGGCAAGCUGUGAUAGUGUUUGGGUGGCUGUUCGGCUGGCCCAGACCAGGCCGAACCGGACCAGACUUGAAGUAGAAGCGCGUGGAGCAUCACCUUGUCCUCGUUCACUCUGCUCGCGUCCUGGGAGUCCCCCGUCCCCCGUCUUGAUCCAAGUCAAGGGCCUACUGGCGCGAGAGUCGCUGGCCCCCGCGCGGGGUUUGGGCAUCUCGGCACGCCGGCUCUGUCGUGGCCUCAGGGGAACAUUGUCGCUUUCGCUACCCGCGGGGCCGGGCGAGCGGGAAGCUCGGCACAGUGGGAGCCUGGUGGUGGGUCUCCUGGGGCCGGUCGCAAUGGGUUUCCGGGGGUCCCGCGGCUGCUCUGUGGACCCCUUCGGCCCCUGGUGCUCCGGGCGCUGGCAGCGUCACCGGACAAAGGCCACCGAGCGCGGGGGUGUCCCCGAGGUGGACGCGCGGGUUUACUUCCUCUCCGGCCCCACGGGCGCGCUUCCCUCCUGACGGAUUCCGAAGCCCGCCCCACCACCGUCACCGCACCAGUGGCCCAGGCUUCGUGGGACCAACAGGGCUAAUCCUGCCCCACGGAUCUAAUCCGGAUCGGGACCCGGUCCCAGGGGAGGCCCCCACCUCCCCUUCUAUUGUUCUGUGGCCCAGGUAUCAAGAGAAGAAAACCGCCAACUGUAUCAGAGUGCUUAUUUAUUGGGCAUAAAGACCACCCGGGCUGGGUGCAGUGGCUGAUGCCUGUAAUCCCAGCACUUUCGGAGGCCGAGGCGGGCAGGUCACGAGGUCAGGAGUUCGAGACCAGCCUGGCCAACAUGGCGAAACCCCGUCUCUACUAAAAAUACAAAAAUUAGCCGGGCGUGGUGGCGGGCGCCCGUAAUCCCAGCUACUCGGGAGGCUGAGGAGGAGAAUCCUGUGAAUCCGGGAGGUGGAGGCUGCAGUGAGCCGAGAUCGUGCCACUGCACUCCAGCCUGGGAGACAAGAGCAAGACUCCGUCUCAAACAAACAAAAAAACACCCAUAUCUCAAACGAGAAAAUGCUUGCAAAUAACCUGAAACCGCGGAACACUAUUCUUUUUAAAACGAGAUAUUUUAAGUAGGUCGUGAAAGUGGCCUUAAUGUUAUACUGCCUUAUUCCAGUGACGAAUAUUCAUCAUGUGUAAAAUGGGAGAAAUGAAAUGUUAUUAAAACAAACAUGUGAGACUUCGAUGAGAAGAGACGGUACCCGGUCUAAGCGCCCACCGGGUCGCGAGGAUCCUUUUCCUGGUUAAGGCCUGGGUCACAGCGAAAGAACCCUAGGCCCAGGGAGGGCCCCGAGAUUUCAGAUCCGGGGCCCGGCUGUGCAGGUGGACCACGCGGAAGGGGCGCUGGGGGCGGUAGGUCGAAAGCAGCCGACAGGGCUACCACUGGCGCACCUGUCCACUUACGGGGACCACCGCCGCAUCCCCGCCCCAGCUAGUCGGUCCUUUCCGGAAGUUCCACCUCCCUAAAUUUUUUUCCGGUUCCGCUUACUCCUUCCGGUCACCAUGGCGACCAGGCGCCUUGGGGUCGGGGAGACGCUGGGGGCCCUCAACGCGGCCCUGGGGCCAGGCGGUCCGGUGUGGAUCAAGGAGACGCGCACCCGCCACCUGCGUUCCCGAGACUUUCUGGCACCGCACCGCGCGCUGCAGGCGCGCUUCGAUGACGGCCAGGUUCCGGAGCAUUUGCUCCAUGCCCUCGCCUGCCUGCAGGGCCCCGGUGUGGCCCCGGUGCUGCGCUGCGCGCCGACCCCCGCGGGUCUGUCUCUCCAACUGCAGCGGUCCGCCGUCUUCGAGCGCGUCCUCAGCGCCGUGGCCGCCUAUGCCACGCCCGCCUCGCCUGCCUCGCUGGGCCAGCGCGUCUUACUACACUGCCCAGCACUGCGCAGCUCCCCCUGCGCACUCCGCUUGAGCCAGCUGCGUACGGUGCUCGUGGCCGAUCACCUGGCGCGAGCCCUGCGCGCUCACGGGGUGUGCGUGCGCCUAGUGCCAGCUGUGCGGGAUCCGCACAUGCUGACCUUCCUGCAGCAACUGCGGGUGGACUGGCCCGCUGCCUCGGAGAGAGCUUCCUCCCACACCCUGAGGAGCCACGCCCUUGAAGAACUUACCUCUGCUAAUGACGGGAGGACACUGUCCCCUGGCAUCCUAGGCAGACUGUGUCUGAAGGAGCUGGUGGAAGAACAGGGCCGCACAGCUGGCUAUGACCCCAACCUGGACAACUGUCUGGUGACUGAGGAUCUCCUCUCUGUGCUGGCUGAGCUGCAAGAGGCUCUAUGGCAUUGGCCCGAGGACAGCCACCCAGGCCUGGCUGGGGCCUCAGAUACUGGUACAGGCGGCUGCCUGGUUGUACAUGUUGUUAGCUGUGAGGAGGAGUUCCAGCAACAGAAGUUGGACCUGCUUUGGCAGAAGUUGGUUGACAAGGCUCCACUCAGACAGAAGCACCUCAUCUGUGGCCCUGUGAAAGUAGCUGGUGCACCUGGCACUCUGAUGACUGCCCCUGAGUACUACGAGUUCCGGCAUACCCAGGUGUGCAAGGCCUCAGCACUGAAGCAUGGUGGGGAUCUGGCACAAGACCCAGCCUGGACAGAGAUCUUUGGUGUUCUCUCUGUGGCCACCAUCAAGUUUGAGAUGCUGAGCACAGCCCCACAGAGUCAGCUCUUCCUGGCUCUGGCUGACAGCAGUAUCUCCACGAAGGGCACAAAGAGUGGCACCUUUGUCAUGUAUAAUUGUGCCCGUCUUGCCACACUCUUUGAGAGUUACAAGUGUAGUAUGGAACAAGGUCUGUACCCCACUUUUCCUCCUGUGAGCAGUCUGGACUUCUCACUGCUACAUGAUGAGGGUGAGUGGUUGUUGCUCUUCAACAGUAUCCUCCCCUUUCCGGAUCUGCUGAGCCGGACAGCAGUGCUGGACUGCACAGCCCCGGGGCUCCACAUUGCUGUACGCACAGAGAUGAUAUGCAAGUUCCUGGUACAGCUCAGCAUGGAUUUCAGCUCCUACUACAACCGGGUACACAUCCUGGGGGUGAGCACACAGCAAAAUGGGGUGGGACGUGCAGAGAGGUAUAGGGUAAAGGCAAAGGAAGCAGAGGAUGAGACCAGCAGGCCCUUUCUCUUUCAGGAGCCUCGACCACACCUCUUUGGUCAGAUGUUCGUCCGCCUGCAGCUUCUGAGAGCUGUGCGUGAGGUGCUCCAUACUGGCCUGGCUAUGCUGGGUCUCCCUCCACUGAGCCACAUUUAAGGCCACAGAGGCUCCAAUACCUGGGAAUGUUCACAAAGUCAUCAACUGGAAAAAAAGCAAAAACCCACGGCCAAAAUAAAUUGGUACUGUUUGUUACAAA